AGUGGAAGAAGAUGGCGGAAGGCGGAGCGGCGGAUCUGGACACCCAGCGGUCUGACAUCGCGACGCUGCUCAAAACCUCGCUCCGGAAAGGGGACACCUGGUACCUAGUCGAUAGUCGCUGGUUCAAACAGUGGAAAAAAUAUGUUGGCUUUGACAGUUGGGACAAAUACCAGAUGGGAGAUCAAAAUGUGUAUCCUGGACCCAUUGAUAACUCUGGACUUCUCAAAGAUGGUGAUGCCCAGUCACUUAAGGAACACCUUAUUGAUGAAUUGGAUUACAUACUGUUGCCAACUGAAGGUUGGAAUAAACUUGUCAGCUGGUACACAUUGAUGGAAGGUCAAGAGCCAAUAGCACGAAAGUGUCAACACUCAAAGAAUGGACGAAAAGAAAGCAAGGAUAUAAGCAGAAAAUACGAUGGAAUCAAAAUCCAAGAGAAACAGCAGACAAUAGAAACAGACCCAUAAGAAACCCAGGUAAUUGAGUUAGUAGAUUUUAGAAUAGUGGGCUUAUUAUGCUUAAAAAAAAAAAAAAAGGCAGAUGAGAAGUAGGGCAAAACUAUUAAAGAAGAAGCAAAUAGAAUUCUAAAACUAAUAAUAUGGAAAUUUUAUGGAUUUAAUGUUUGGGAAUAAAAUUAUUAGACCAAACAGAACUGAAGAGAAAAUUUGUAAACUAAAUGAUUUGUCAAUAGAAAAUAUAGAGUCUAAAGCUUAGAGAGACAAAAGAAUAGAAAAUACAGAAAAAAGCUAAGGCAUAAAUGGAAUGCAGUAAGUAAGUUUAACAUGCAUACAUAUAGUUGGAAUCUUGGAGAGGAAAGAAAGAGUGGGUAGAACUAAUACCAAAGGACGUAAUAGCUGAGAAUUUUCCCAAACUGAGAAAGGUGUCAUGCUUUAAAGAAAUGCUAUGAAUCCCAAACUGAAAUAAUACAAACAAAACUGUACCUAGUACAAAUGUUGAAAAGCAAAGGCAAAAAAAUUUCUAAUAAUAGCCAGAGAAAAAGACAUGUUAUCUUCAAAAUAAGGAUAAGACAAAAUAAUGAUUUCUCAAGAGAAACCAUGGAAGCCAGAAAACAAUGGACUUUGAUAUGUUAAAAGAAAAUAACUGCCAAUGUAGGAUUCUGUGACUAAGAAAAUAAUCCUUCAGGGAUGAAGGUGAAAAAAGCCAUUUUCAAAUGAAAACUAAUAGAAUUUGUUACCUGCAGACGUGUAUUAAAGGCACUACAAAAUAAUCUUAAGAAUGGAAGGAAAAUUAUUCCAGAUGAAAGCUUGGAGAUGCAGGAAAACAGUGUAGACUGACAAAAUGUAAAUGUUGUGAGUAAGUCUUAAGAUGGACUGUUGAAAACAUUAAUAAUAAUUUUUAUGGAGUUGAAAAUGUGUAUAGAAUUAACUACACAAUAGUGUUAGCAUGUAAGUUAAGAUAAUAUUCUCUACUAUGUUCCCUGGUGAUCCCCAGCUCCUCAUAUCCAUAUUCUUGGGCACUCUUCUUCCAUGUUGUACUGAGGUUGGUCUGUGUGGCCAAUAGCAUAUAGCAGUACUCAUGGUACAUCGCUUUCGAGAUUAGGUUAUAAAAAAACACCGCGGCUUACAUCUUGGGUGCACACGCACUCUAGCUGUCUCUCUUUCUCAUUUCUCACUCGGGGAAUUCAACUGCAUAUGGCGAGGACACUCAGGCAGCCUAUGGAGAGGCCCACAUGGUGAGGAACUGAGAUCUCUGGCCAAUAGAGAGGAACGGAGGCCUGCAACAACCAUGUGGUUGAACAGGGUAUGUUUGUAAAGCACUGCAAAGUAGAAGUAUAUCUCACAGAAUUGAAGCUAUGUGAAAAUGGAAACAUGAAUAAUGUUGUAACUCGAAGAUUUAGCAAAGCUGACACAAUAGAUACAAUUGAAAAGGAAAUAAGAAAAAUCUUCAGUAUUCCAGAUGAAAAGGAGACCAGAUUGUGGAACAAAUACAUGAGUAACACAUUUGAACCACUGAAUAAACCAGACAGCACCAUUCAGGAUGCUGGUUUAUACCAAGGACAGGUAUUAGUGAUAGAACAGAAAAAUGAAGAUGGAACAUGGCCAAGGGGUCCUUCUACUCCUAAGUCCCCAGGUGCAUCCAAUUUUUCAACUUUACCAAAGAUCUCUCCUUCAUCUCUAUCAAAUAAUUAUAACAACAUGAACAACAGAAAUGUGAAAAACUCAAAUUACUGUCUUCCAUCAUAUACCGCUUAUAAGAACUAUGAUUAUUCGGAACCUGGAAGAAACAAUGAACAGCCAGGCCUCUGUGGCCUAAGUAACUUGGGAAAUACGUGUUUCAUGAACUCAGCUAUUCAGUUACCGGUUUACUAAAAUAGUGAGCAUACAUGAUCACUUGAGAAUUGGGCUUCUGGAGCACCUGAACAGAAAGGGAGUGGUUCAUAUUCAGCAUUACAAAAGACAACUUUCUCUUUUUGAAGGGGAUUACUUUGGCUAUUUUCCAGUGUUUGAGCAACACACCUCCACUUACUGAGUAUUUCCUCAAUGAUAAGUAUCAAGAAGAACUGAAUUUUGACAAUCCCUUAGGAAUGAGAGGUGAAAUAGCUAAAUCUUAUGCCGAACUGAUCAAGCAAAUGUGGUCUGGAAAGUUUAGCUACGUCACCCCAAGAGCCUUUAAGACACAGGUAGGACGUUUUGCACCUCAGUUCUCUGGAUAUCAGCAGCAAGACUGUCAAGAACUGUUAGCUUUCCUAUUAGAUGGAUUACAUGAGGAUUUGAAUAGAAUUAGGAAAAAACCAUAUAUACAAUUAAAAGAUGCAGAUGGAAGGCCAGAUAAGGUGGUUGCCGAAGAAGCCUGGGAAAACCAUUUAAAACGAAAUGAUUCUAUCAUAGUAGAUAUAUUUCAUGGCCUUUUCAAAUCAACUUUAGUUUGUCCUGAGUGUGCUAAGAUUUCAGUAACAUUUGAUCCUUUUUGUUACUUGACACUUCCAUUGCCCAUGAAAAAAGAACGCACCUUGGAAGUUUACUUAGUUAGAAUGGAUCCACUUACCAAACCUAUGCAGUACAAAGUGGUUGUCCCCAAAAUUGGAAACAUAUUAGAUCUUUGUACAGCAUUGUCUGCUUUGUCAGGAAUACCUGCAGAUAAGAUGAUAGUUACUGAUAUAUACAAUCAUAGAUUUCACAGAAUAUUCGCUAUGGAUGAAAACCUUAGUAGUAUUAUGGAACGGGAUGAUAUUUAUGUGUUUGAAAUUAACAUCAAUAGGACAGAAGAUACAGAGCACGUGAUUAUUCCUGUUUGCCUAAGAGAAAAAUUCAGACACUCGAGUUAUACCCACCAUACUGGUUCUUCACUUUUUGGUCAGCCCUUUCUUAUGGCUGUACCACGAAACAAUACUGAAGACAAACUUUAUAAUCUCCUGCUCUUGAGAAUGUGCCGAUAUGUCAAAAUAUCUACUGAAACUGAAGAAACUGAAGGAUCCCUACACUGCUGUAAGGACCAAAAUAUUAAUGGGAAUGGCCCAAAUGGCAUACAUGAAGAAGGCUCACCAAGUGAAAUGGAAACAGAUGAGCCAGAUGAUGAAUCCAGCCAGGAUCAAGAACUUCCCUCAGAGAAUGAAAACAGUCAGUCUGAAGAUUCAGUUGGAGGAGAUAAUGAUUCUGAAAAUGGAUUAUGUACUGAGGAUACUUGCAAAGGUCAACUCACGGGACACAAAAAACGAUUGUUUACAUUCCAGUUCAACAACUUAGGCAAUACUGAUAUCAACUACAUCAAAGAUGAUACCAGGCAUAUAAGAUUUGAUGAUAGGCAGCUUAGGCUAGAUGAAAGAUCUUUUCUUGCUUUGGAUUGGGAUCCUGAUUUGAAAAAAAGAUAUUUUGAUGAAAAUGCUGCUGAGGACUUUGAAAAACAUGAAAGUGUGGAGUAUAAACCUCCUAAAAAACCCUUUGUGAAAUUAAAAGAUUGCAUUGAACUUUUUACAACAAAAGAAAAGCUAGGUGCUGAAGAUCCCUGGUAUUGUCCGAAUUGUAAAGAACAUCAGCAAGCCACAAAGAAAUUGGAUUUAUGGUCCCUGCCUCCAGUACUUGUAGUACAUCUCAAGCGAUUUUCUUACAGUCGAUACAUGAGAGACAAGUUGGAUACCUUAGUUGAUUUUCCUAUCAAUGACUUGGAUAUGUCGGAAUUCUUAAUUAAUCCAAAUGCAGGUCCUUGCCGCUAUAAUCUGAUUGCUGUUUCCAACCACUAUGGAGGGAUGGGAGGAGGACACUAUACUGCUUUUGCAAAAAAUAAAGAUGAUGGAAAAUGGUACUAUUUUGAUGACAGUAGUGUCUCCACUGCAUCUGAAGACCAAAUUGUGUCCAAAGCAGCAUAUGUACUCUUCUACCAGAGACAAGACACUUUCAGUGGAACUGGCUUUUUUCCUCUUGACCGAGAAACUAAAGGUGCUUCAGCUGCCACUGGCAUCCCAUUAGAAAGUGAUGAAGAUAGCAAUGAUAAUGACAAUGAUAUAGAAAAUGAAAACUGUAUGCACACUAACUAAUGAAAGUCCUAGAAGCCAUAAAAGAGACACUUUCCUGCUGGUGGUAUCUAUGGAAAUGAUGAAGUUACCCACCACAUUAAAACAAAAGUCUGAGAUGGGGAGUUUCAGAUAACCGAAUGUAAAUCCUUUAUCAGAUUUUAACUUGUGCAGUACUUGAAGUGAAACACAAUGAAAACUUUAACAGAAAUUGUCUCUUAAUACAUUUACAGUCUUGUAUUUACAAGCUAAAUAUAUAUAGGAAAUCACAAAUAAAUCCCUUUUAAGUUUGCUGCUGUUUUGAUUAAUUAUGUUUCCUUUAAUUUUUUGGAUGUGAGUUGAUGACAAAUGUUAAAUUUGUGGAUGUUGGUCAUUUAUUUUGCUCUAAUAAUACUGCAAGAAAACUAUGGCUGAACUUAGUUUUUGGAUAAUCUAGUUCAUGUGCAUUAGGCUGCCGUAUAUACUACUAUGAUAUUUAGCUGCAGUAUCAAUGUGGCAUAAAUACUGCGGCAGCAUUCUUCGAAAACCGCAUUUUCAAAUUUAUCCCCGUAAUCAAUGUGGGCCUAUUAAAAAACCAAAUCAUGAUACAAGAAACAACCUUGGAAAAGUUAUUUCCCUUUGUAAUACCUUUAAAAAUCCAGAGUAUUAUAUUCAUUUUACUGCCACUGUGGAAACAGGUUCUAGAUUUCAUACUCCAUCUAAAGUCAUUUUUCAGUUACAUGUAAGUAUUAUUUACUGCUAUUGGGAUCUAUUCUUCAGAUAUUCAAAAACAUUUUUUGCUUUAAAAUGCAUAUCUUUAAUUGGGUGUUGGUCCAAAAUUAAAAUUUUUGCUGUCUGUUUUUCUCUACCCCAUUUUGUGGUAAUUUGGCAACUUGAGCUCUCCCAAUUAUUGUAAUAUAAGGACAGACAUAAUAGUAUUCUGUACCCAUAGUAAUAAUUGCAUCAAGCUUAGAUGAGAAAUUUUUUUCAUAUACUGGCCUUUAAAUCAUUAAUGGACAAUUGGCUAUAAAGGUAGGUCUGUUAACUUUCUUUGUGUGUUCCUGAUGGAAUUCACCAUAGCCUUACAGCUUUUCUCAGAAGGUAACUUGUUAUAAGAGAAAUGGCAUUUGCAUGUUCCAGAGUCAGAACCUGUACAGUAUAUAAAGCAUAAACACCUUGAAUUUGAUUUUAGUUCACCACAUUCAAGGAUCCAGGAUGCCAAAAAUAUGUGUGAACAUUUGAAACAUUUUUAUUUGCUGCUUUUUCCCUUUGAUAUAGUUGAAAGAAUGUAUUGUAAAUUGGCAUACAAUACUGCCUUUAAUAGAAAACCUAAAUGCUGGGGCACAUUUCACAUAUCGACUACCUGAGAAAUUGCUUUGUGUCCCACUGUUAUUAAAGCAAAAAGUAUAAUGUUCUUCACUUGAACUAAUCAAAUACAAUAGAUUAUAAAUUGUGUAUUGUAAAUAAAAGUUCACUCUGUGAGUGCACAUUUUGGUAAAUUAUUUAUUUAUGUUAGCAUUUAAAAGUUUAAAAAAAAUGCAUUUGACCAGGAUAAAUGAGGUAUGUUGAUCAUGGCUUUGCUUUAUAUCUUGAUAUUAAAGCUGGUUUAUCAUCCUGGUAUUUUAAAAGCUGCUUUGGGGUUUUUUUUUUCUUUUUUUUUUUUUUAAUGUAAACUAACCUCCUGCAUGACAGAGGUUAAAAUUUUGUCUGCACUUGAGUUCACUUGAGUUUACAUUUGAAAUGUGCAUGUUUAUUUAUAUAGAUUUCAAUAAAGCUAUUCAAGGCCUUAUUUAGUCUUUUAUUUCUUACUCUUAAUCUUUUAAUAAAAAUCCCCUACUUUAUGGUUAGAUGACUAUAUGCUAGACUUUUUAGUUAUAAAUAGUUAAUACUAGAAAGGAAAUUAUGUCAGAGCAAAAUGAAUCCUACUAUUAAGGACGUUUUAAAGUUGAUUUUUGUCCACUUUAAUAUUUAUUCAUUAAACAUAUGUUUGUGUACCAAUCACUGUUGUAGAGUCUGGAGAUACAGCAGUAAACAAAUAUCCUUACCUUCACAGAGCUUACAUUCUUUCUGCCAUCUACCAACUAAUGAACUAUAUUUCCAUUUUUCUGAAGAUUUAAAGAAAAGUCAAAGCUAAAUCUUUUAAACCUAUAUUGUGGUCUCCAUCCUAAUUCUUCAGAGACCACUUUCUUUUUAAUGCCUGUCAUUAACUUCUGUUCCCACUAAAAGAAGUGAUGUUAAUAAUGCCAUUGAAACUGCCAAACUCAAAUGUCAUUUUUCAGCUGCAAGAAGUAUACUUUAAAAAUAGUGCAAAAGGAUAAUACAUAUUCUAAUUAAAAGUAGGCAUUCAGACUGGGCACGGUGGUUCAUGCCUGUAAUCCCAGCACUUUGGGAGACUCAGGCGGGAGGAUCACUUGAGCCCAGGAGUUUGAGACCAGCCUGAGUAACAUAGUGAGAACCUCAUCUGUACAAAUAUAUGUAUUUUUUUUUAAUUAGCUGGGUGUGCACACACCUGUGUUCCCAGCUACUGGGGAGGCUGAGGUGAGAGAAUUGCUUGAGCCCAGGCAGUCAAGGCCGCAGUUAGCCGAAAUCACACCCCUGCACUCCAGCCUGUGCAACAUAGCAAGACUCUGUCUCAAAAAAAAAAAAGAUAUUCAUAGGUAAUACAGGGUAAUGGGAAUAUAUCUAGACUAGAAUUUCUACUUCUAGCUUUGCCACUUAGCAAUCAUAUGACUUUGAACUUAAUCUUUGAUAGUGUUUCUUUACCUGUAGAAUAAUGAUGAUAAUAGCCAGCAUUUAUUGAGCACUUACUAUGGACCAGGCACUAUAUUAAAGUGUUUAUAUGCAUUCUCUCAUUUAAUCCCACAACAGCUAUGAGGUAGGGAUAGUUGUCAUCCCCAUUUUUCAUAUGAAGAAACCAAGAUACAAAGCAUUUAAGUAAUAUUCCCAAGCUCACACAAUUGCUAUGGGGUAGAGCCAAUAUUCUAUCCUCAGAUAUAUACUACCUCUCACUGUGUUAUAGUGUCUGCCUCAUAGGAUUGUUGAGAGCUCAAAUGAGAUCAUGUAUUUUAUGGGAAGAGCUUUGUAAACUUUAUUACACACUCACUGAUUUCUUCAGUCUAAAUAGAAAGACAUCUUGAAGUCUAAUAACUUUGCUUCUAAAAGUAUAUUUAGCUCAGUAUUCGAGCAUUGAAUAAGAAAGUACCCACUGGAAUAUUGACUAACCCAUUCCCUUUUAAAAAUUAAUUUCAUUUAAUUUAUAUACCUUUAUUACAAUUUUAAUUAAAUGGUAAAUACAAUGUGACAUUUUUUUCUUACCUUUUCAUCUAACUUGUGUCCCCUUCUUUCCAUUUCCCCAAAUGCAACCCUGAAUUUCAGGACUUUGUAAACUCUACUCUAGUUUUGCUUUCUGUUUGUUUGUUUGUUUGUUUAGAGACAAGGUCUCCCUCUGUCGCCCAGGCUGGAGUGCAGUGACAUAAUCAUAGUUCACUGUAACCUUGAACUCCUGGGUUAAAGUGAUCCUCCUGCCUCAGCCUUAUAAUUUAGUUUUAAUUAACCUCCUUGAAAAAGUUGCAGCCUGGUGCUUUAUUUAAAUAUCUUGCUUUCUCAUAAUCUGUGUUAUUUUAGUAGUCCUGUAUUUAUCCUUGCUUUCCUGACAACUGGAUAUAAAACUACACAAAACAUUGAUUUGGGCACAAAGAAAAUCAGUAAGUACCAAAAUAGAUACAACAUAAAGGUGGUGGGGUUUUUUAUGAACUAAUUUGAUUGAAGUGAGUUUAUCUUAUAAAAUAAGCCGGGAGACUGAAAUGGAGUCUCCUUCAGUGGUACACCAAAGGGAGUGUAGGGUGUAGUAGGAGCUCUCUGCCUCCGAGAGGAGGAAUAUAUUAGACUGAUAACGUUUAAGUCUGAUGUAUGGUGACAAGAAAAAGGCCAAUUUUUUGUUUUGUUAUUUUUAAGUUACCUACAGAUAAUGCAUUUCAUUAUUGCCUACUUCCAACUCUCCCUAUGUAGUAUGUUUCUGAUCUUCUGUGCUUGUGCAGUGUAGAUGAGCUCACCGCUUUAAUUUUUAAGAUAGAAAUGUGGAAAACUCUUGAAUCAUAGACUAGGGGAAGGAACCAGAGGUCCUCUAAAAUAUCAGAGGAGUGAGAAGGAAAGGAAGAGCUCCUUUCUAGGGCCAUAGAAUAAGAGUAGAAGUUUUUGCUCAUUUUUUUUGUUUGUUUUUACUUUACAAAAAAAUAAAAAAUUUUUUGCUCUUUGAAUAACUUAACAUGAGGAAUUUGGAAACAACCUCUCUUGAAAAUAUAUUGGUAUUCAUUCCCAAAUAAUUCUUCUAAGUACCACUUGACCAGAGGAUAGGGAAAGGAGGAAAAGGUGAGUGUAUUUAUAUCCUUGCUAGUUUUUGUUAUAUAUUCAGUUGCAGAUCUAUAUUAUAUAUCAUUUUAUUAUCAGAUUUUCUAGUGAGAAAUAUAUAUGAUGGUUUUUUAAUAAUCAUUUUAGGUUUGGAGGCCAUUUCAAUUCAAUAUGUAUGUGUUUUACGUGUUUAAUUCGUAUUUACUAUAUAUUAAAAGAAUUUCCAAAUAGCUCAGAUAAGAAAACUUUGGUUUAAAAUUGAGUUAUUUUAUAAGCUACAUAGAAUACAUCAAAAUUUUAUAAGCUGCAUAGAAUAGGCUUUAAAAUAUCAGAAUUAGGAAAAUAAAAUAUAGAUGGUAAAAAUUCAAAUAUUUAUCAAGACUUUUUUCUUCACUAAUGAUGGGGUAAAGAAUUUUUAAAUGGAUAAUAUAAAACAGACAGUUCAAAAAUUAUUUUUGGAAAAUAUAUGCAUCGGGAAACAUACCCCACACGGUGCCAUGGUUUAAUUAUUCCCCAGCUCUACUUUUGGGAGCCUGGAACUUGUCAGGGUUGUGAAAUAGAUCUCAGACUAUUAAGGACAUUCAGAAACUGGCUAAGCCAUUCAAGGAAAAUCAGGAAUUUACGUAAUAUAUUGGACUACAGUCUCAAAGGACAGAGAGAAAAUCAGUCAAAUGGGUUUUGAUAUUUUUUUUUCCUAGAAAUGUGUAGCAAAUGUGAUUUUACAAAGCAGCUAAAAAUACAACUAUCUCUCUGGAAUUGAAAAUGUGUAAAAUAAGACCACACACUUUCAAUAUGCACAAAAUAUAUUUUAAAUGUUUAAGUUGUAUUGGUAAUUUACUAUGUUCUCCUGUAGAAAAUCAUAAUUAAAGUUGGUGCUCGUGUUGCUAAAGUUUUUUUUCUCAUGUCAGGAACUUGCAGCUUGUUCUAUAUAGUUUGGUGAAACAAACAAAACAGUUUUUAUCUGCUGUGACAUUUAAGUUUGUUGUUAGCUGGAGUUAAAUCUACAUACAUAAAAGUAAAACAAUAAAUAUGGAAACAUCCCAACAGUCUUUCCCACAAUGUGUAUUAUUACAUUAUUCUCAGUAAUGACACAUACUUAACAUUUCCCAAGCUGUUGUUUUAAACCUUAAACAUCACCACAUUUCUAAUUUUUAUUUAAAAUCUUUCAGAAUUCUUAGAUUUUGUAACAUAUCAAGCACAAGUCUCUCAUUAAAAUUUUUUUUUAAUAGUAUUUGCUUUUCUUUUAAACUCCAUAAAGGAGUAUUCGAUGUUAACAGACGUAACUCUUUAAUGCUCCUCUGUUCAUGAUUAAGUAUGCUAAGUUUUAAGUAAUUUAGACUAAUGUAUUAAAGUGUUCACUUAUGUCUAGUCAUAUGCAUACCUACUCUCUUCUAACCUUGAGUCAUUUCUAUUAAAUACAGCAUUUAAUCUUCUUUCAAGUGAGAACCAUCUUUCCAUUAUAUCAAGUGGGCAAUAUUUAAAUUGUCUGAUAAGUUCAUCCAAAUUAAUCCCAUCAUGCCUGUUUAACUCAUUUCCCCAAAAAGACCGCGACCUCCAGCCAGUCAUUCAGUUCUUGAACUCCCUAAUAGAAGCACCAAGGAUUAUCUAUUUGUAAUCACAUUGUGGUGAAUUAUCAGUCUCCCAAGAAUUAUGUAAAGCAAAUAGGAAUUAUUUUAGAGUUGCCCUUAUUUUAAAAAACAAAAAAAAAGUAAAGAUGGGAAAAUUACUUAUAGUAUUUUUUUUUAAUUUGAGAAAGAAUUCCUGUAGGUCUCCCUUAAAUAGUGACUUUGGUAAAGCUUUUUAAUUUCUAGAACUCAGAGCUAUAUUCACUUUUGAGCUAUGUACCUAUUGUAUAAGUUGAAGUAAUACUGCAAAUUCAAACAGUAAACAUCAUUAAUCCUAGAUAUUUGGGUACUACCUACAGUGAGAUAUGGUAGGAAACAUUCUACACUUACAACAACUUCCACCAUAGCUAGCUCCAAACAGGUCAUUAACCUCUGAAUUACUGUUUUCACAACCAUAAAAUUAUGCUGGUCUCUUGAAAGUAUUAGUUUAUGGGUGUGGAGAGGAAGGCUUAAAUUUCAUUUUUGAAGCUGUCGUUAAAAGUAUAUAUUUUUAGCAAAGGAAUUAAUAACUAAUAGCAUUGAUGAGUCAAGUUAAUAUUUGUUUUUGUUUUUUUUUUUUUUUAAUUUUGGGCCUCACUCCUAUAAAAGACUUGGAACAGAAGUCUUAGUAUGAUGGUAAACUUGAAAAUUAAAAUUUUAUCAGGGAUAUUAGAAUCCAAUUAUAUGAGACUGCAUCCUCAACAGGCACCUUGGUUGCAACACCAUGAAAGACCUUGAUCCAGAGGUUCUCAGCAAGCCACACCUGAAUUCCUAACCCACAAAAACUGUGAGAUAACAGAUGUUUGUGUUUUUAGCUGCUAAGCUUUAAUUUGUUUAUGCAGAAAUAAGGGAAAAGGACCCUAGAGAUCCUUGAGGAAUCCCACUUUACAGAUGUAGAAGCUGAGGGCUAGAAGGAGAAAAGUCAUGUACACAAAGUCUGGAGACAACUCAGAUAGUCACUACAUCCUCUUGCUCUUUCUCAUUUUUACUCUUUAACUGGCUCCUCACUUUUUAGAUGGAUGGCACUGGGCUCUGGAGCAAACCAUCUGUUCUGUAUCUGUUAAGGCCUCUAGAGCUUCAUUCAUUCCUUCAUCAAAUAUUUUUUGAGUGUCCACUAUGUGCCAGGCACUAUUCUAGAUUCAAGAUAUAAAGUAAUAUACAAAAACAAAAUCCAGUUACAAAUAUAAUUUUUAAAGCUAUUUGUGAGCAUAACUUCGUAACACAUUUAGAACCUUUGCCUUCAGCUGACAUGAAUUAUGUUGUCUUUUUGUUUUUUGGUCCAGUUUCAUUAGUCAUUAAAGUCAUUUGAAUUAAAGACAAUAAUCCAGACUCCAGAGGUUAUGGCUUUUAUGUGUUUGGAUACUGUCAUAGUCUGCUCAGGCUGCCAUAACAAACACAGACUGGGUGGCUUAAAUAACAGAAAUUUAUAUUUUCACAGUUCUGGAGGCUGGGAAUCUGAGAUCAGGGUACCAGUAUACUGGGUUUCUGGUGAGGGUGCCUUUCCUGGCUUACAGAUGGCUGCCUUCUCACUGUGUUCUUGCAUGGUAGCAGAGGAGGGUCAGAGAGGAGAGCAAGCUCUGAGGCAUCUCUUUUUUAUAAGGGCACUAAUCCCGUCAUGAAGCCCUCACCCUCAUGACCUCAUCUAAACCUAAUUAUCUCCUAAAGACUUCCUCUCCAAAUACUAUUUAAGGCUUCAACCUGAAUUUGGAGGUGACACAGUUGAGCCCAUAGCAGAUAUAUUUAGUAACAACUGUGGGUACAGGCAUGCCUCAGAUAUUGCAGGUUCGGUUCCCAGCCACCAUAAAUAUUUAAAUAAAGUGAGUCACAAAUUUUUUGGUUUCCCAGUGCAUAUAAAAGGCAUAUUUACCCUAUACUGUAGUCUAUUAACUGCAAUAACAUUGUGCCUAAAAAAGAUGUACAUGCCUUAAUUUUCAAACUAUUGCCAAAAAAUGCUAAAUAACCAUCAGAGCCUUCAGCAAGUAGUAAUGUUUUUGCUGAUGGACAGUCUUGCCUCAUUUUGAUAGAUACUCACCAGGAUGGUGGUUGCUGAAGGUUAGGGUGGCCGUGGCAAUUUUUUACAAUAAGACAGUAGUGAAGUUUGCUUCAUCAAUUGACUCUUCCUUUUACAAGAGAUUUCUCUGGCAUGCAGUGCUAUUUGAUAAUAUUUGAUACCCACAGUAGAACUUCUUUCCGAACUUCUUUCACAAUUGGAGUUAAUCUUCUAAAGCCCCGCCACUGCUUCAUCAACUAAGUUUAUGGAAUAUUCUAAAUCCUUUGUUGUCUUUUCAACAAUGUUCACAGCAUCUUCACCAGGAGAAGACUUUCCCCCCUUCUUUUCACAGAUGUUGAGAUUGUCAAGAAACUACUUUCCUUGCCCACCCAUAAGAAGCAACUUAUCAUCUGUUCAAGUUUUAUCAUAAGAUUGCAGCAAUCCAGACACAUCUUCAGGCUCCACUUGUAGUUCUCUUGCUAUUUUCACCGCAUCUGCAGUUACUGCCGCCACUGAGGUUUUGAACUUCUCAAAGUCAUGAAAGUUGUAAUUAACUUCUUUCAAACUCUUGUUAAUGUUGAUAUUUUGACUCCCAUGAAUCACAAAUAUUCUGAAUGAAUGGCAUCCAGAAUAGCAAAUCCUUUUCAGAAGGUUUUUAUUUUGCCCAGAUCCAUCAGAGGAAUCACUAUCUAUGAAAGCUUUUGCCUUAUAAAAUGUAUUUCUUGGAUGAUAAGACUUGAAAGCUGAAGUUAUUCUUUGAUCUAUGGCUGCAGAAUGGAUGUUGUGUUAGCAGGCAGAAAAACACUAAUCUCAUACAUCUCCAUAGAGCUCUUGGGUGACCAGGUGCACUUGUCAAUGAGCAGUAAUAUUUUGAAAGGAAUCUUUUUCUGAGCAAUAGAUCUCCGCAGUGGGCUUAAAAUAUUUAGUAAACCUUCCUAUAAACGGAUGUGCUACCAUCCAGGCUUUAUGGUUCCUUUUAUAGAGCAAAAACAUUAUAUUUAGUUUAAUUUUAAGGACCCUAGGAUUUUUGGAAUGAUAAAUGAACAUUAGUUAGCAUUGCAUUGGCCCCUAACAAGAAAUCAGUCUCUCGUUUGAAGCCAAGCAUCAACUUUUCUCUAGCUAUGAAAGUCCUGGAUGACAUCUUCCAACAUAAGACUUUCAUCUACAUUGAAAGUUUGUUUUUAGUGUAACUACCUUCAUCAAUGAUCUUAGCUAGAUCUUCUGGAUAACUUGCUGUAGUUUCUACUUUAGCAGUUGCUGCUUCACCUUAUGCUUGUCUGUUGUGGAGACAGCUUGUUUCCUUAAACUCCAUGAAUCAACCACUGCUAGCUUCAGACUUUUCUUCUGCAGCUUCCUUACCUUAGCCUCCAUAGAAUUGAAGAGAGAGGGCCUUGCUCUGCGUUAGGCUUUGGCUUAAGAUAGUGUUGUGGCUGAUUUGAUCUAUUAAAAAAAAAAAAACUCAGGCUUUCUCUAUACCACUUUUCUUAUGAUUCAUGUGUUCACUUGAGUAGCACUUUUAAUUUCAGGAACUCUUCCUUUGGAUAUACAACUUGGCUGUUUGGCUCAAGAGGCCUAGCUUUCAGCUUGCCUUGGCUUUCAACAUGCUUUCCUCACUAAGCUCCAAUCAUUUAUAGCAUUUGAUUGAGAGAGAGAGAGAGAUGUACAGCUCUUCACCUGAACAUUUAGAGGCCAUUGGAUGGUUAUUAACUGGCCUGGUUUUAAUAGUGUUAUGUCUCAGGGAAUAGGGAGGCACAUGGAGAGGGAGAGAGAUGGGGAAUGGCCAGUGGAGCAGUUGGAACACACACGUCUGUGCCCUCAAACAAAACAGUAACAUCAAAGAUUACUGAUCACAGAUCACCGUAACAGAUACAAUAAUAAUGAAGACAUUUGAAAUGUGAGAAGUACCAAGAUAUGACACACACACAGUAAGCACAUUCUGUUAGGAAAAUAACACCUAUAGAUGUGCUCAAUGUAGGCUUGCCACAAGCCUUGUUUGUAAAAAAACAAAAACAAUUAUCUUCAAAGCAUGAUAAUAAAGUGAAGCAGAAUAAAACAAGGUAUGCCUGGUUUUUGUUUUGUUUUGUUUUGAGACAAGGUCUUUCUCUGUCACCCAGGCUGGAGUGCAGUGGCACAAUCUCAUCUCACUGCAGCCUCCAGCCUCUGGGCUCAAGUGGUCCUCCCACCUCAGCCUCCGAAGUAGCUGGGUCUACAGGCAUGUGCCACCACACCACACCUGGCUAAUUUUUGUAGAGACCAGGUUUCACCAUGUUACCCAGGCUGGUUUUGAAGUCUUGAACUCAGGCGAUCCAUCCACCUCGGCCUCCCAAAGUGCUGGGAUUACAGGCAUGAACCACAGCACCUGGCCAUGUAUUUUCAUUUAACCAGUACUAAAUAACUACAUGUCUUUGGCAGCCUAUAAUGUAGCAUCCCAUUUUUAAAAAUAGAAGUGUGUAUUCAGGGUGCACUCAAUAGGAUUACAUCUGGCUGGCAGUCCCUUCCUACUUCAGUCCAUUAUCCUGCUACCAGAAUGAUCUUCAUGGUUUCAUUUAAAAAAAAAAAAAAUGAGAUCCUGUUUCUGUCUUAAAGUUCUCUUCUAAUUCCUUGUAUUAAUCAGGAUUCUCCAGAGAAACAAGACCAAUAGGAUGCAUAUGUGUAUACACAUAUAUGUAUAGCUCUCUCCCUCAUAUAUACACAUAUCAUGUAUAUACAUAUAUAUCAUAUAUGUACAUAUAUAUAUAUAUAUAUGAGGGAGAGAAAGAUUUAUAAGGAAUUAGUUCAUGCACUUAGGCUGAGAAGUCUCAUGAUCUUCAGUCAGCAGGCUGGAGACCCAGGAAUGCCAAUGGUGUAGUUCAAGUCCGAGUCCAAAGGGUUGAGAACCAGGAAAACCAAUGAUAAAAGUUCCAGUCCACAAGCUACCUGGCUAAAGACCCAGGAAGACUGAAUGUUUCAGUUUUAGUGCAAAGGCAGGAAAAGACUGAUGUCCCAGUUCAAUCAGGCAAGAGAAAUUAUCCUUACUUGAGCCUUUUUUGUUCUAUUCAGGCCUUCAAUUCAUGAGAGCCACCAACAUUAGAGAGGGCAAUCUGCCUUACUCAGUCUACUGACUUAAAUGUUAAUCUCAUCCAAAAACACCCUCAUAGAUAUGCCCAGAAUAAUGUUUGACCACAUAUCUGGGCACCCUGUGGCCCAGUCAACACAUUAAAUAAACCAUCACAUCCCUUCAUGUAGAAAAGAGUGGUUUGGACCAUAGGCUCAGGAGUUAAACCACCUCUGAGCCUACCACUUUUGUGCAACUCACCUCACCUCUCUGCCUUUCACCUCUCUGUAAACUAGAGCAGCUCCCGAAUGUCCAUCUAGGAAGGCUUGGGGUGAGCAACCUGAUUAGAAGGGAACAAUGUGACUUAAAACUGCAUAUUUGCUUAGCAAACCUAUGACUUUUCUCAGAAUAUACAGUUUGCUUGUGAUGGAGGGCUAUUAAUAUUUAUAAGGAAACCAAAUCCCCAUUCACUUAAGCCAUCCACUCCUACCACUGUAAUUGAAUAUUACCUACCUUUCAGAAUAAUUGCAAGGUUUUGUGUCUUGAUCAUUAUGAAAAAUGUGGCAGGUAUUAUUACUAAUAAAGAAGUACCCAACUAUGGGAAUGAUUGUUCCUUCCUUAUGAAUGAGAGCAGCUCUCUGUUCAAUACGAUUCAUACUCAAGUUCUAAUAAACUUUCUUUAGCAAGAGAGCAAAGAGUAUGGUACAGUCAGUCCACCCAGGUUGCCUGUUAACCUGGUGCUUGAAGGAAAAAAAGUAAGAAUUUGCCCUCAUCUAAUUCCUCACUUGCCCUCAAACAUGUCAUACUACUUGACAAUGGGGCUUUCCCACAUUUGUCCCACAUUUGCAUGGUCUGCCUUAUCUCUUACCUGGCGAACUCCUACACUCCUUCAAGACUUGCUCCAAAAUGCACUUGCUAGAUCUUCUGACAUCAACUGCCACCUUGGGCUAUAAGUUACGUGUGUCUCUUCCCCCACUAGACAAUUACCUGAUGGAAGAAUAUUGUUCUUAAGAUGUUAAGAUGGUGUAUGUGUGGCAUAGUAUUUGUUCCUAAAUGUAAAAGUUAUUAAACAAGUUUUCUGAAA